AGACCAGCACGGCCUCGCGGAGCCGGCCCGGCGGACCGUGACGGGUCCCCUCACCUCCUCUUCUCUCCCCUCCCCGCCCGCCCUCUCUCCCUCCCUUCCUCCCUCCCGCUCGCUUCUUCUCACGCCGGGAGCAGGCUCCCGCCUCGCACCGCUGCCCCGCGAGCAGCUCCUCUUCUCCCGAGGCGCGCGGGGCGCCCCCGCGAGCCCCGCGGCUGAGACCCCGCAGCCUGGAGGAGGGCUGUCCGGGGCUUUGGAUGCUGCUGCUAGGGGUGGUGGGAGCAGCCGUGGGACGCGUGGCCGGGAGCGGGGGUGACAGCCUGGGAUUCCGGGGGCUUCUCUUCCUUGUCCUCCUCCUCUCCUCUCUAUUCCCAGUGUGGCCGUGGCUGACACUAAAGACUUUGUAGCCAUCAACCCGAGUGCAGUUUCGAUGGAAAAUGAAGGUUGCACGUUUUCAAAAAAUACCUAAUGGUGAAAAUGAGACAAUGAUUCCUGUAUUGACAUCAAAAAAAGCAAGUGAAUUACCAGUCAGUGAAGUUGCAAGCAUUCUCCAAGCUGAUCUUCAGAAUGGUCUAAACAAAUGUGAAGUUAGUCAUAGGCGAGCCUUUCAUGGCUGGAAUGAGUUUGAUAUUAGUGAAGAUGAGCCACUGUGGAAGAAGUAUAUUUCUCAGUUUAAAAAUCCCCUUAUUAUGCUGCUUCUGGCUUCUGCAGUCAUCAGUGUUUUAAUGCAUCAGUUUGAUGAUGCCGUCAGUAUCACUGUGGCAAUACUUAUCGUUGUUACAGUUGCCUUUGUUCAGGAAUAUCGUUCAGAAAAAUCUCUUGAAGAAUUGAGUAAACUUGUGCCACCAGAAUGCCAUUGUGUGCGUGAAGGAAAAUUGGAGCAUACACUUGCCCGAGACUUGGUUCCAGGUGAUACAGUUUGCCUUUCUGUUGGGGAUAGAGUUCCUGCUGACUUACGCUUGUUUGAGGCUGUGGAUCUUUCCAUUGAUGAGUCCAGCUUGACAGGUGAGACAACGCCUUGUUCUAAGGUGACAGCUCCUCAGCCAGCUGCAACUAAUGGAGAUCUUGCAUCGAGAAGUAACAUUGCCUUUAUGGGAACACUGGUCAGAUGUGGCAAAGCAAAGGGUGUUGUCAUUGGAACAGGAGAAAAUUCUGAAUUUGGGGAGGUUUUUAAAAUGAUGCAAGCAGAAGAGGCACCAAAAACCCCUCUGCAGAAGAGCAUGGACCUCUUAGGAAAACAACUUUCCUUUUACUCCUUUGGUAUAAUAGGAAUCAUCAUGUUGGUUGGCUGGUUACUGGGAAAAGAUAUCCUGGAAAUGUUUACUAUUAGUGUAAGUUUGGCUGUAGCAGCAAUUCCUGAAGGUCUCCCCAUUGUGGUCACAGUGACGCUAGCUCUUGGUGUUAUGAGAAUGGUGAAGAAAAGGGCCAUUGUGAAAAAGCUGCCUAUUGUUGAAACUCUGGGCUGCUGUAAUGUGAUUUGUUCAGAUAAAACUGGAACACUGACGAAGAAUGAAAUGACUGUUACUCACAUAUUUACUUCAGAUGGUCUGCAUGCUGAGGUUACUGGAGUUGGCUAUAAUCAAUUUGGGGAAGUGAUUGUUGAUGGUGAUGUUGUUCAUGGAUUCUAUAACCCAGCUGUUAGCAGAAUUGUUGAGGCGGGCUGUGUGUGCAAUGAUGCUGUAAUUAGAAACAAUACUCUAAUGGGGAAGCCAACAGAAGGGGCCUUAAUUGCUCUUGCAAUGAAGAUGGGUCUUGAUGGACUUCAACAAGACUACAUCAGAAAAGCUGAAUACCCUUUUAGCUCUGAGCAAAAGUGGAUGGCUGUUAAGUGUGUACACCGAACACAGCAGGACAGACCAGAGAUUUGUUUUAUGAAAGGUGCUUACGAACAAGUAAUUAAGUACUGUACUACAUACCAGAGCAAAGGGCAGACCUUGACACUUACUCAGCAGCAGAGAGAUGUGUACCAACAAGAGAAGGCACGCAUGGGCUCAGCGGGACUCAGAGUUCUUGCUUUGGCUUCUGGUCCUGAACUGGGACAGCUGACAUUUCUUGGCUUGGUGGGAAUCAUUGAUCCACCUAGAACUGGUGUGAAAGAAGCUGUUACAACACUCAUUGCCUCAGGAGUAUCAAUAAAAAUGAUUACUGGAGAUUCACAGGAGACUGCAGUUGCAAUCGCCAGUCGUCUGGGAUUGUAUUCCAAAACUUCCCAGUCAGUCUCAGGAGAAGAAAUAGAUGCAAUGGAUGUUCAGCAGCUUUCACAAAUAGUACCAAAGGUUGCAGUAUUUUACAGAGCUAGCCCAAGGCACAAGAUGAAAAUUAUUAAGUCGCUACAGAAGAACGGUUCAGUUGUAGCCAUGACAGGAGAUGGAGUAAAUGAUGCAGUUGCUCUGAAGGCUGCAGACAUUGGAGUUGCGAUGGGCCAGACUGGUACAGAUGUUUGCAAAGAGGCAGCAGACAUGAUCCUAGUGGAUGAUGAUUUUCAAACCAUAAUGUCUGCAAUCGAAGAGGGUAAAGGGAUUUAUAAUAACAUUAAAAAUUUCGUUAGAUUCCAGCUGAGCACGAGUAUAGCAGCAUUAACUUUAAUCUCAUUGGCUACAUUAAUGAACUUUCCUAAUCCUCUCAAUGCCAUGCAGAUUUUGUGGAUCAAUAUUAUUAUGGAUGGACCCCCAGCUCAGAGCCUUGGAGUAGAACCAGUGGAUAAAGAUGUCAUUCGUAAACCUCCUCGCAACUGGAAAGACAGCAUUUUGACUAAAAACUUGAUACUUAAAAUACUUGUUUCAUCAAUAAUCAUUGUUUGUGGGACUUUGUUUGUCUUCUGGCGUGAGCUACGAGACAAUGUGAUUACACCUCGAGACACAACAAUGACCUUCACAUGCUUUGUGUUUUUUGACAUGUUCAAUGCACUAAGUUCCAGAUCCCAGACCAAGUCUGUGUUUGAGAUUGGACUCUGCAGUAAUAGAAUGUUUUGCUAUGCAGUUCUUGGAUCCAUCAUGGGACAAUUACUAGUUAUUUACUUUCCUCCGCUUCAGAAGGUUUUUCAGACUGAGAGCCUAAGCAUACUGGAUCUGUUGUUUCUUUUGGGUCUCACCUCAUCAGUGUGCAUAGUGGCAGAAAUUAUAAAGAAGGUUGAAAGGAGCAGGGAAAAGAUCCAGAAGCAUGUUAGUUCGACAUCAUCAUCUUUUCUUGAAGUAUGAUGCAUAUUGCAUUAUUUUAUUUGCAAACUAGGAAUUGCAGUCUGAGGAUCAUUUAGAAGGGCAAGUUCAAGAGGAUAUGAAGAUUUGAGAACUUUUUAACUAUUCAUUGACUAAAAAUGAACAUUAAUGUUAAAGACUUAAGACUUUAACCUGCUGGCAGUCCCAAAUGAAAUUAUGCAACUUUGAUAUCAUAUUCCUUGAUUUAAAUUGGCUUUUGUGAUUGAGUGAAACUUUAUAAAGCAUAUGGUCAGUUAUUUAAUUAAAAAGGCAAAACCUGAACCACCUUCUGCACUUAAAGAAGUCUAACAGUACAAAUACACUAUCUAUCUUAGAUAGAUAUAUUUUUUUUUAUUUUUAAAUAUUGUACUAUUUAUGGUGGUGGGGCUUUCUUACUAAUACACAAAUAAAUUUAAUCAUUUCAAAGGCAUUCUAUUUGGUUUAGAAGUUGAUUCCCAGGAGUGCCAUAUUUCAGCUACUGUAUUUCCUUUUUCUUGUAAUGUAAGCAGCUCAGAUACCAUGUGCUAUCAUUUUUGUAUCAAGUUUUUUGCACAGGAUGUGACCACUGUCAGAUCACUGUUCUUUUCUUUCUUUUUGUGAUUGAAAAGCCUAUACUACAAUUUGAAGUAAAUUUUUGUUUUUCUUAGUAAGUGUAAAUGGUUGCUUUAUUUUUAUUUUAAAAAGGUAUGUCUUUGGUUUGGCAGAAUUCAUGCAGGGCUAUCAAGUGGUGUUCUAGGGUAACAGUGUCCAUAAUUAACGCUUAGUCAUAGAGUCAAAAACAUUUAAGACUGAUUGGGUUGAAGUUUAUAAUAAAUUAUAUUAACAUGUCUUCCUUUUUGAGGUAAAGAUAUAUACUUUGUCAAAUAUCAUUUUGUCAUCCUCUAAAUAUAAAUCCAAAUACCUCAGCUAAGUAAUUCUAUUUUAUUAUUUUUACUGUUAUGUAUGUUUUUAAUCAUAUUUCUUAGGAAGUAUAGGCUACUGGACUUAGAAUAAAAAGUCCCCAAACCCAAACAAAUGGUUUAUGAACCAGAGUAUAUGUGGAAGAUUCUUUGCUGGUCUUGCUCUGUGUGCAUCUGAAGCUUCUUUGGCCUAGAUUUUAGCACAAACCUGAGUAUAUCUCUUCUACUUUCAUCAUGUGUUCUGUACCUUCUUUUUGUUUCAUUGGGCAUGCUAGGGAAAUAGGUGGAUUUUGUGUGUAAUGCCAUCAGUUUUUAUGAAAGCUUGAUGAGGUAUAGGUCAUUUGUUUUGAGUAUGUGGGCCAGAAAUUUAAAAUUAGAAAUUUGUUUUUCUGUUGAGUAUAUAAACAAAAAUUGGUCCCAAUUCUAACAGGUUUAAUCCUUCUUGAAGCCAAUAAGUUUUAUCUUUUAUAAUCUGUCAGGAUGAACCACUCCUUAGCUUUUAUCCAAUAUUAAACUGCAAGUGUUAGCACUGAAAUAUUGUCAUUGAUAGGGAAAAUAUCUAUUCUUUGAGUCAUUGUUACUGAGGCAGUUGAGUGUAAGGAGCUGGCUGCAGUUUAUUCUACUUAACCCUUUAAGGCUGAAUUGUCAAAUGUACAUUGUUCCAUGUCGUUAGAUGGAACAUGGAAGCCAUUGUCUAAUCAACUCUAUCAUUAGUGACUUGAUGUCUCAUACCUUAAUUUUGUAAUGAUUUUUAUUCUCUGUUACAAAGACUUGAAAUACGUAUUAAAUGCACGUUAAUGUUUUGCUUUGCAUUUUAGGUUCAGAUUAUGACUUGAUUGAAAUAAAUGUGCCUAUACAUUCAUUUGCUUUGUACUAUAAAAAUAAAAAUGAUUUCUUAAGUUAA